ACUCCCACUUCCUGAGCUCCGCCAUGGGAGCCCUGGAGGCCCGGCCUGGCCGCUCCCGGCCCUGGGGUGCACAUCGGCCCUGAGUCCCGUCCCAGGCUCUGGGCUCGGGCAGCCGCCGCCACCGCUGCCCAGGACGUCGGGCCUCCUGCCUUCCUCCCAGGCCCCCACGUUGCUGGCCGCCUGGCCGAGUGGCCGCCAUGCUCCUGCCUUGGGCCACCUCUGCCCCCGGCCUGGCCUGGGGGCCUCUGGUGCUGGGCCUCUUCGGGCUCCUGGCAGCAUCGCAGCCCCAGGCGGUGCCUCCAUAUGCGUCGGAGAACCAGACCUGCAGGGACCAGGAAAAGGAAUACUAUGAGCCCCAGCACCGCAUCUGCUGCUCCCGCUGCCCGCCAGGCACCUAUGUCUCAGCUAAAUGUAGCCGCAUCCGGGACACAGUUUGUGCCACAUGUGCCGAGAAUUCCUACAACGAGCACUGGAACUACCUGACCAUCUGCCAGCUGUGCCGCCCCUGUGACCCAGUGAUGGGCCUCGAGGAGAUUGCCCCCUGCACAAGCAAACGGAAGACCCAGUGCCGCUGCCAGCCGGGAAUGUUCUGUGCUGCCUGGGCCCUCGAGUGUACACACUGCGAGCUACUUUCUGACUGCCCGCCUGGCACUGAAGCCGAGCUCAAAGAUGAAGUUGGGAAGGGUAACAACCACUGCGUCCCCUGCAAGGCCGGGCACUUCCAGAAUACCUCCUCCCCCAGCGCCCGCUGCCAGCCCCACACCAGGUGUGAGAACCAAGGUCUGGUGGAGGCAGCUCCAGGCACUGCCCAGUCCGACACAACCUGCAAAAAUCCAUUAGAGCCACUGCCCCCAGAGAUGUCAGGAACCAUGCUGAUGCUGGCCGUUCUGCUGCCACUGGCCUUCUUUCUGCUCCUUGCCACCGUCUUCUCCUGCAUCUGGAAGAGCCACCCUUCUCUCUGCAGGAAACUGGCUGCUUAUUCUGAGGCUGGAGAUGAGAGUGACAGUGGCUUGUUCCUCUGGGCCCCCGGGUGGUCAAGUUGCUACACAUUGUGCUGGGAUGUGGAGGCUGAAAGGCUAGGUCUGAGGCCUGCCGGGGAGCCUACACCCAUUUCAUUCUCCAUUGCAGGAUCGCUGCUCAAGAGGCGUCCGCAGGGAGAGGGACCCAAUCCUGUAGCUGGAAGCUGGGAGCCUCCGAAGGCCCAUCCAUACUUCCCUGACUUGGUACAGCCACUGCUACCCAUUUCUGGAGAUGUUUCCCCAGUAUCCACUGGGCUCCCCGCAGCCCCAGUUUUGGAGGCAGGGGUGCCGCAACAGCAGAGUCCUCUGGACCUGACCAGGGAGCCGCAGUUGGAACCCGGGGAGCAGAGCCAGGUGGCCCACGGUACCAAUGGCAUUCAUGUCACCGGCGGGUCUAUGACUAUCACUGGCAACAUCUACAUCUACAAUGGACCAGUACUGGGGGGACCACCGGGUCCUGGAGACCUCCCAGCUACCCCCGAACCUCCAUACCCCAUUCCCGAAGAGGGGGACCCUGGCCCUCCCGGGCUCUCUACACCCCACCAGGAAGAUGGCAAGGCUUGGCACCUAGCGGAGACAGAGCACUGUGGUGCCACACCCUCUAACAGGGGCCCAAGGAACCAAUUUAUCACCCAUGACUGACUGAGUCUGAGAAAAGGCAGAAGAAGGGGGGCACAAGGGCACCUUCUCCCUUGAGGCUGCCCUGCCCACGUGGGAUUCACAGGGGCCUGAGUAGGGCCCGGGGAAGCAGAGCCCUAAGGGAUUAAGGCUCAGACACCUCUGAGAGCAGGUGGGCACUGGCUGGGUACGGUGCCCUCCACAGGACUCUCCCUACUGCCUGAGCAAACCUGAGGCCUCCCGGCAGACCCACCCACCCCCUGGGGCUGCUCAGCCUCAGGCACGGACAGGGCACAUGAUACCAACUGCUGCCCACUACGGCACGCCGCACCGGAGCACGGCACCGAGGGAGCCGCCACACGGUCACCUGCAAGGACGUCACGGGCCCCUCUAAAGGAUUCGUGGUGCUCAUCCCCAAGCUUCAGAGACCCUUUGGGGUUCCACACUUCACGUGGACUGAGGUAGACCCUGCAUGAAGAUGAAAUUAUAGGGAGGACGCUCCUUCCCUCCCCUCCUAGAGGAGAGGAAAGGGAGUCAUUAACAACUAGGGGGUUGGGUAGGAUUCCUAGGUAUGGGGAAGAGUUUUGGAAGGGGAGGAAAAUGGCAAGUGUAUUUAUAUUGUAACCACAUGCAAAUAAAAAGAAUGGGACCUA